AAUCCCCACUUCCGACCCUCUCAGGCCUUUUCCGCUUCUCUUUUACCUCCCCAGGUCCGCCCGUCUGCGCCCCUCACAGGAAGCCGGAGGGUCGCUCUGAUCCCGAAUCUCCCACAGGCGUGAACCUGCUCUGCUGUGUAUCUUUGCGGGGUGGCCUGCGCUGAGGCCUGCCGCGCGCGGUGAGUCCGCGCAGACCUGACCCUGCGUCUCGCAGCUCGGUUGAGGCCGCCGCCGCCUUCUCGGGAUGCCGCGGCCGGGGUCCGCGCAGCGCUGGGCGGCCGUCGCGGGCCGUUGGGGGUGCAGGCUGCUCGCACUGCUGCUACUGGUGCCUGGACCCGGCGGCGCCUCUGAGAUCACCUUCGAGCUUCCUGACAACGCCAAGCAGUGCUUCUACGAGGACAUCGCUCAGGGCACCAAGUGCACCCUGGAGUUCCAGGUGAUUACUGGUGGUCACUAUGAUGUAGAUUGUCGAUUAGAAGAUCCUGAUGGUAAAGUGUUAUACAAAGAGAUGAAGAAACAGUAUGAUAGUUUUACCUUCACAGCCUCCAAAAAUGGGACAUACAAAUUUUGCUUCAGCAAUGAAUUUUCUACUUUCACACAUAAAACUGUAUAUUUUGAUUUUCAAGUUGGAGAAGACCCACCUUUGUUUCCUAGUGAGAACCGAGUCAGUGCUCUUACCCAGAUGGAAUCUGCCUGUGUUUCAAUUCACGAAGCUCUGAAGUCUGUCAUCGAUUAUCAGACUCAUUUCCGUUUAAGAGAAGCUCAAGGCCGAAGCCGAGCAGAGGAUCUAAAUACAAGAGUGGCCUAUUGAUUGAAAAGAAAUGCUGAGAAAUACAUAAAGUUUUCCUCUUCUGCCUUGGAUAUUUAUAAUGGGUAUCGGGAAGUCUAAAAUAAAUUCCUGCCCUCUUUCUCUCUCUUGGGGUAAAAGGCACAGUGUGGAUACAAGUCCAGGAUAUCAUGAGUCAGAUUCCAAGAAGUCUGAAGAUCUAUCCUUGUGUAAUGUUGCUGAGCACAGCAAUACAACAGAGGGGCCAACAGGAAAGCAGGAGGGAGCUCAGAGCGUGGAAGAGAUGUUUGAAGAAGAAGCUGAAGAAGAGGUGUUCCUCAAAUUUGUGAUAUUGCAUGCAGAAGAUGACACAGAUGAAGCCCUCAGAGUCCAGAAUCUGCUACAAGAUGACUUUGGUAUCAAACCCGGAAUAAUCUUUGCUGAGAUGCCAUGUGGCAGACAGCAUUUACAGAAUUUAGAUGAUGCUGUAAAUGGGUCUGCAUGGACAAUCUUAUUACUGACUGAAAACUUUUUAAGAGAUACUUGGUGUAAUUUCCAGUUCUAUACGUCCCUAAUGAACUCCGUUAACAGGCAGCAUAAAUACAACUCUGUUAUACCCAUGCGGCCCCUGAACAAUCCCCUUCCCCGAGAAAGGACUCCCUUUGCCCUCCAAACCAUCAAUGCCUUAGAGGAAGAAAGUCGUGGAUUUCCUACACAAGUAGAAAGAAUUUUUCAGGAGUCUGUGUAUAAGACACAACAAACUAUAUGGAAAGAGACAAGAAAUAUGGUACAAAGACAAUUUAUUGCCUGAGAUGAAACAUAUAACAUGUGGCUGGCUCUUGUUUUGUAAACCAAAUGAUUAAUCUUCACUUGAGAAAGCAGUUUCUAGGAAAUGUUUAAAUAAAAGAGAGUCUUCACCUUAAAGAAACCUAUGGAGCACAAGAAAGAUAAAUUUCUGCAGGACAGCCUAUAAAAUUGUGGUACUUUUUGAUGUUUCAGUAAACUUGACAUUGUCAGAGUUUCAAGGACUUUUCUUUCACAAUUUUCCUAGUUCAUGGAUAUGAAAAAGGAAUUCUCAAUCCAUAUUCCUUGUAUUGAACCUUGAACAAAAACUUGUAUGACAGACAUUUUUAAAAAUGUGACAACACUUUUAUUCUCUGAAUUUUGAUCUCAAAGGACACAGAAAAAAAAUGGCCCCAGGAGAUCUGAUCACACUUCCUCCUGAGGCACCUCUCAUGGAUGUUGCAAUAAGCAUUCGGGUACUAUCACCCAGAAAUAUGAAUUGCCAGAAUAGAACAUUUAGCAUGUUAAGCGUUGAUGCAUAUAAAAUCAGAAAUAGAUGUGAGAAUGGUGGAACUUUUUAAAAGAACCCAGUCAAAUGUAUUUUCUGCUGAAAUCUGCAUAUUUGGAGGCAUUUCCCACCACCGAUUCACAGCCCAUUUGAUAGUGUGGUAGUUAGGGACUUCGUGGAGUGGUGUUCAGACGUCCCCUGGGGCUUAAAUCUCUUCAUAUUAGUCAUCAUUUGUAACUAUGGCUUUAUUUGCAGAGCUUCUAAAAGGCGUAUAACUGUGUGAGUGGCCAGAUAUUCACUUUUUAAAUCAAAAACCUCUCUUAUGGAAGCUUUAAAAGUUUCCGUCACACACAAUUCUCUUCUCAGGAAGUAUUUCUCAUUUAGGUCUUCAAAGUAGCCUGACUGUGUGCAUGUGUGUGUGUGAUAGGUUAUUUAUAAAGACUUUGGAUAGAAGGAGAUGUAUUUUAUUACCUCCUAUUCUAGAGCCCCAUGCUCCUAACAAGCCAGAGAGGCCCCAAACAGGAUUGUUUCUUUCCUCCACAGCCCUUCUGCCCAUCUGAGAUUGAGGGAGCAUCGUCCACUUGAGAUCAGGGAUGGGGUGGAGAAUGGGUCAUGUCAUGUAAUGAGAAAAGCCCUCUUCGGGAUCAUGAGACUUGGUUCUAGUCCAAUUUCUGCCACUGAGGAUGAAUGUAACUGUGGGCAAACUAUUUACCCUCCUUUAUCUGUGAAAUGAAAGGGUUGAAUUGAUGGAUCUCUAAAGGCUUUUGUCCUCUAUGAGGAUGUGAAAAACUAGGGACCACAAAAGGGAACAAGCAAAAAAGUUUGGAUUCGAUAAAGUGAUAUGUAAUAGUUGCAGAAGGCUUUAUAUAUGCUUAUAAUGAAAAGAUAUUUUUUGUAUAUUGACAGCAUAAUUUAUUUUUAAUGCUGUCAUUACACUUAAAGUCACAGGAAAAAAAUAUACAUGCUUACUCAGGCUUUCUUAAAAAUAAAUUUUUAUAGAGAUCCUUGAGUAAAGACAUUUUGCUUAAUUUCUUUUUUCUUAUUCCCCACUUGUAUAUCCCCUACCAGUACCGGGAUCUGCACACAUCUUUUUGCAGUUACCUCUUCAUAGCCAUGAACCAAAACGUUCUAUGAGGAGCAUGCAAGUAAGUCAAGCCUCCUAUUCUGUUAGUACUUAUUAGAGGAGGAGAUGGUUUUCAUUGCAUAGUGACAUUUUCUUAGCCUUAACGUUCUGAUAGUAGCUUACUACUCACUUCUCUUUUUCAGUUUUCAUAAUAAGUAUUCAUUUUUUUGCCAUAAUGCUUCCUGUAAAGCCAAUUUUAUAUACUAAUAAAACAUGAACUGCCCACUCUUCAUGCCUGCCAAACUUGGGGCAAUUGAUGCUAAAUGGUAUUUUUAAAAUAAAUGUUUUUAUUCUUUACUCUUGACUAAACUUGUUUAUUUUCAACUCCAAUGAAGAUUGUGGAAGAGUGUUUUGAAAUGAAGCAUCGAUUUGUACUUCAUAGAGCACCAGACACAAUGUCUCACCCAAUUUGGAGUUCCAUAUUUUUUUUAUGAUAAAGAAAAAUGUUGG